AGAUAUUAAUCACGGAGUUCCAGGGAGAAGGAACUUGUGAAAUGGGGGAGCCGGCUGGGGUUGCCGGCACCAUGGAGUCACCUUUUAGCCCGGGACUCUUUCACAGGCUGGAUGAAGAUUGGGAUUCUGCUCUCUUUGCUGAACUCGGUUAUUUCACAGACACUGAUGAGCUGCAAUUGGAAGCAGCAAAUGAGACGUAUGAAAACAAUUUUGAUAAUCUUGAUUUUGAUUUGGAUUUGAUGCCUUGGGAGUCAGACAUUUGGGACAUCAACAACCAAAUCUGUACAGUUAAAGAUAUUAAGGCAGAACCUCAGCCACUUUCUCCAGCCUCCUCAAGUUAUUCAGUCUCGUCUCCUCGGUCAGUGGACUCUUAUUCUUCAACUCAGCAUGUUCCUGAGGAGUUGGAUUUGUCUUCUAGUUCUCAGAUGUCUCCCCUUUCCUUAUAUGGUGAAAACUCUAAUAGUCUCUCUUCAGCGGAGCCACUGAAGGAAGAUAAGCCUGUCACUGGUCCUAGGAACAAGACUGAAAAUGGACUGACUCCAAAGAAAAAAAUUCAGGUGAAUUCAAAACCUUCAAUUCAGCCCAAGCCUUUAUUGCUUCCAGCAGCACCCAAGACUCAAACAAACUCCAGUGUUCCAGCAAAAACCAUCAUUAUUCAGACAGUACCAACGCUUAUGCCAUUGGCAAAGCAGCAACCAAUUAUCAGUUUACAACCUGCACCCACUAAAGGCCAGACGGUUUUGCUGUCUCAGCCUACUGUGGUACAACUUCAAGCACCUGGAGUUCUGCCCUCUGCUCAGCCAGUCCUUGCUGUUGCUGGGGGAGUCACACAGCUCCCUAAUCACGUGGUGAAUGUGGUACCAGCCCCUUCAGCGAAUAGCCCAGUGAAUGGAAAACUUUCCGUGACUAAACCUGUCCUACAAAGUACCAUGAGAAAUGUCGGUUCAGAUAUUGCUGUGCUAAGGAGACAGCAACGUAUGAUAAAAAAUCGAGAAUCCGCUUGUCAGUCUCGCAAGAAGAAGAAAGAAUAUAUGCUAGGGUUAGAGGCGAGAUUAAAGGCUGCCCUCUCAGAAAACGAGCAACUGAAGAAAGAAAAUGGAACACUGAAGCGGCAGCUGGAUGAAGUUGUGUCAGAGAACCAGAGGCUUAAAGUCCCUAGUCCAAAGCGAAGAGUUGUCUGUGUGAUGAUAGUAUUGGCAUUUAUAAUACUGAACUAUGGACCUAUGAGCAUGUUGGAACAGGAUUCCAGGAGAAUGAACCCUAGUGUGAGCCCUGCAAAUCAAAGGAGGCACCUUCUAGGAUUUUCUGCUAAAGAGGCACAGGACACAUCAGAUGGUAUUAUCCAGAAAAACAGCUACAGAUAUGAUCAUUCUGUUUCAAAUGACAAAGCCCUGAUGGUGCUAACUGAAGAACCAUUGCUUUACAUUCCUCCACCUCCUUGUCAGCCCCUAAUUAACACAACAGAGUCUCUCAGGUUAAAUCAUGAACUUCGAGGAUGGGUUCAUAGACAUGAAGUAGAAAGGACCAAGUCAAGAAGAAUGACAAAUAAUCAACAGAAAACCCGUAUUCUUCAGGGUGCUCUGGAACAGGGCUCAAAUUCUCAGCUGAUGGCUGUUCAAUACACAGAAACCACUAGUAGUAUCAGCAGGAACUCAGGGAGUGAGCUACAAGUGUAUUAUGCUUCACCCAGAAGUUAUCAAGACUUUUUUGAAGCCAUCCGCAGAAGGGGAGACACAUUUUAUGUUGUGUCAUUUCGAAGGUUGAGCGGUUGAAAUUAUUUUCUCUAAAGCAGACACACUCUUGGAUAACUACUGAGUUCCUGUUAUAGCUCAGCAAGAAAAAAUGCUUAUGAUCCCAGUACUCCAGACAAAGGUCCAAAGUGCUUCUGUUCUUUUGACUCUCCUUAAAGAGUUUUUACCACCAACAUAGUAAUCUAUUCGGCUUUCUUUGCUUAGUUCCAGUUAUUUGUAGCUUAUUUUCCUGUAAAUACUUUGCCUUUUUCUCCUCUCUUUGAUUUGUUUGUUUUAGUAUGAUUUGGAGAGGGAGGUUGGAGAAUAACUUUUUCUCAAACUUCCAAGUCACUUUGAGUGUAGAAUAACUGAUACAUUAAUAAGAAAAAAAUCCAAUUAAGUUUAAUGCCUUUUUUGUUUGUUUGUUUGUUUGUUUUAAGAGACAAGGUCUCUGUUGCCCAGGAUGGAGUGCAGUGGUACAAUUAUAGUUCACUUCAGCCUCCAACUCCUGAGCUCAAACAGUUCUCCUGUGUCAGUCUCCAGAGUAUCUGGGACUACAGGAGAGUGCCACCACAUCCAGCUAAUUUUUAUUUAUUUUUUGUAGAGAUGGGGUCUCACUUUGUUGCCCAGGCUUGUCUUGAACUCCUGGACUCAAUAAUGCUUAUUUUAAAAAUACUUUUGUGGCCAGGCGCGGUGACUCACGCCUGUAAUCCCAGCACGUUGGGAGGCCGAGGCGGGUGGAUCACGAGGUCAGGAGAUUGAGACCAUCCUGGCUAACACGGUGAAACCCCGUCUCUACUAAAAAUACAAAAAAAUUAGCCGGGCGUGGUGGUGGGCACCUGUAGUCCCAGCUACUCAGGAGGCUGAGGCGGGAGAAUGGCGUGAACCUGGGAGACGGAGCUUGCAGUGAGCCGAGAUCGCGCCACUGCACUCCAGCCUGGGUGACAGAGUGAGACUCCAUCUCAAAAAAAAAAUGCUUUUGUAUGAUAGUCUAUUUAGGGAGGGAGGGAGGAGGUUGAUUAAAUAAUAUAACAAAAUUAAUUCAAGAGCUAAGACAGAAACAAAUACUCAGGAAAGCUCAAAUAAAGUUAAGAAGAAGAUGAUUUUAAAAGGGCAGAAAAGAAACAUUGAGAAGAAAGAUUGGGAAAUGAUAUUAAUUUAUUAUUUCAAUACACAUUUAAAUACCAUCCUUACAUGUAGCUGUCUCAUCCACUAAUAUAUAAGGAAAGAAUUUCUUCCUGGGGCAGUUUUUCAUUAAAAACAGGUUCUCUUUGAAUCAGAUGGCUGUGAAUGUCAGUUUGCCAUAUUAUCUCUACUUGUUUAAUAUUUUUCUUUUGCAAAUGAGAUGGAUGCCUACUUUGGGAACAUUUUUUAUUUCUAUUACAUUUUCUGUUUUCAGUACCUGUCUCAAAUUGUAAGUAAACACGUAAAGUGUCUUUUCAUCAGUUUCAAAUACAUACAUAAUAUUACAGAAGAAUCUGAGCUAUAGCCAUAUGACUGCCUGAGAGAUGUCUCUUUCUCCUCUCUUUCCAAGUAUUUUAUAUAUUCUAGCAAUAGUACCAUAUUUGGGUAUGCACCCCUUACUGGUCCCUUAUAAAAAUUAUUAACACUGUCAUAUAUACGGCAUGGAUUAUAAGGGUAGCCUUAAGUAAUAGGGACUUAUUGUAAGUUAUGUGAGAUUAAAGAAGCACAGGAAACUGGCUCAGAAUCCAAAUAAUCCCUCUGUGCUUGUGCUUCAUUGGGUGGAAUGUAUACUAGUCUUCAUGGAGAAUUGGAAUAGUGGUUUAUUGUCAUUUCUGAUUUGACAGCAGCUCCAGUGAUUCCACUUUAGUCUUUUUUUUACACUUUACUGAUUCAUACUCCUCAAACACAAAGAUCUGAUUGGGUAGUUCUGGUCACCAUCUCUUACGCAGAGAAUUACUAUGGCAGCUUUGGCUUAUGAUCCACAGUUAUUCAUUUGUGACAAGAGAAAAACCUGGGGCCACUCUUCUGAGAAAAUGACUUUGGCAGGCACUGGGAGCUUCAUAAACUACUAUACCACACAGCCUGUUUUUUUUAAUUAUUAUUCUUUUUUCCCCGUUCUUAGUAAGUGUGCAUUAAAUUCUUUCUUGUAUUGGUUCCUAAUUGUUUGAUCUAAAAGGCCCAUCUUCUCAUCUAUAUGAUAAGCCUUUUGAAGGCAGGAAAUAUCGUAUGCUUUUGUGACUACCCCUGACACUCAGCAAUGCCUACCACUGAGUGCUUACUGAACAGAAUGGUUUUAGACAUGAGCCAUUGAGAGAAGUCACAGUGAUGGAAGUUUGUUGUUUUUCAUAAUCAUUUAAAAGGUUUUUUUUUUUACAUUGUUUUGCUUAAAGAAAUUGGAAUCUAUUUUACUGAUCUAAGAAGUAAUAUAAGCUGUGCUGAAUGCCAGUAGAAAGUUUAGUUAAAGAUGAUCUCUGUUUUGUCCAUUUAUGAUUUGCACUAGCCAGAUAUCAUCAGCUUAUUCUUGUCUCUGAAUCUAAGCUGUAGAGCUAAAUAAUUCACCUGAGUGUAGUGUUUAACAGCUUUCUAUGUCAGUAAGUAGAACUUUGAGAUACUUGCAUCUUCAUUUAAAAUUAUUUGUUGGCAGCAUUUUGGAGUAGAUUGUUGUUAGACCUCACUGAUUUCUUUUUUGGAGAAGGGAUGGGUUCUACUAUUUGUACAGAUUCAAGCAGUAGGAGCCAGAAACUUGAAACUUUGGAAACACUGUAGGAAAUACUGUGAUUAUUGCAAAAAAAAAGGUUGACUAGUGGUGUUAUUUGUUCAAAAUGUUUGCCAGAGGUUUAGUCCCACGGAUGGGCAUAAAAACGAAUUUCAAAAAUAGCAAUGAUAUUUUCUAACUUAAUACCUAGAUUAAUACCUAACACAUGAAGAAUGGCAUAUUUUCUUAAUGCCUGUUAUUUAUUUCUUAGAAAUUUAUGUUUAGUUUAUAUGCAUAUAUAAAAAUUCAACAUAUGUAUAUAUAUAAAAAUUCAAUUGUAUGUAUAUAUAUAAAAUCUUCAGAGGCAGGAGGAAUUUCUUUAGUAUCAAAGGAAAUUCAUUUAUAAAGUCUACUUCAAAAGGGUACAGCUCCUUCUUUUGUUUCUGAGACCUCAAAACUUGAGUGUACACAUAGAUGUUGGAGUUUGGCCAUUUUCUUAUCUCCACUUUCAUGGCCUUUGAGCCAAAUUCUAGCUGGAAAAAAAAGUGAAUAGAUGAGUUUGGAAAGAUACUUGCAUUUUAGAAAAGGGUCUUAUCUCAGAAGAGAGAUGUUUUAAAAAACCUUCUUUUAGAAGGCUUUUUAAAAUUAAUUUUUAGCUUUAAAAUAUAUUCUCAUUCAGGUCUAAAGCACAUUAUAAAAAAAUAGAGCAGAGUUGACUGAGUACCCUAGGUUAAUAAACUUAACCUAGAUUUAUUUAAUCAUUAUGCCAAUAAUGUUCUUUUUAUAUGUCCAUUUUCUAUUUCACUUUAUUAUAUACAAAUAUUAACACUUCAAUGUAUACUACCUUUGUAGUUUACAAACCUCUUUCACAUACAUAAUCUUAGCAAUUCCUUACAUAUAAUCACAAGUAUUCUUAGUCCUAUUUUAUGGCUGAAAAAGCUGAAGCAAAGAGAGAUUAAGUAGCUUAUCUAAGGACACAAAAAUGGUAAGCAUUAGAACUAGGGCAAUAAUUGAUAGAUUCUAAUUUAAUACAGUGAUUUUUUUUUCUUUACAUUGUUGUGCUUUUUUCUUUAUAUCUGGCACUUUUAGAUGUAUUACAGCAUAUGUAAAUAAAUUAAUCUAACCCUCCAAAAUCAAGAUAUUUCAUUGAAAAAUCUGCUGGACAGUUUUGGCAGAUUCAUUACACAACUUCAAAAAUUGUUUGUUUGUUAAUUACCUGAUUAUGUUUGUUUGUUAAUUACCUGUUAAUUAUAAUUAUAGAUUAAGUACUUUAAUAGAUUAUGCUUUCAUAAUGCUGGAGAAUAACUUAAUGGUUUGAAAUAUUAUAGUAUAGCUUCAGAUUUCAAGUCAGGGAAUAGAAUAAAUAGGCCUUGAAAGUUUCUGGUUUCUUUUUAAAACAGUGUCUGAAAUUUCCAACAUGGUGGAAAAGAAAUGUCUUUGCUUUGUCUUAAAAAGGAAGUAGUUUAGCAAAAACAGAAGCUGUUUUAAUUAUUGGUAUUCUAGAGCUUCUCAUAGAAAAGAGUGGGGUUUUUGUGUGUGUAAAUACAUUUUAUUAUGGAUUCUGUAUAUGGCGUGCUAGAUCUUUGAGAUCAGAAGCAUUUGAUCUCAAACUCCUUGUUAAAUGUGAGUUACUGUUGUGUGGUUUUAGAGGAUUCAACUAUUUGUUCUUUGUCUCUAUAACAUUGCUAGCUAACAUAAAAACAUGUUUUUUACUUACACUUUUCAAUCACAAAGUCUAAAAUAACUUGCUUUAUGUUUGAGAAAAGAUUGUUCAGUAGUCUGUAAGUAGACUUGUAUAUAGCCACAAACAGAGAACUUAUAACUCAAGAAUAAUACGAAGUCUUCAAAAUUCUCAGAAUGGUGGGCAGAUCCAUCUGAGUCAUGAUAAUUUUUCAAUGGUUCUUAUUUGUUUGCUCUAUUUGGUAGUCUUAUUAUUAUGAAAUGUGUUUUUCAUAUGCAUUUGUUUAAUCUCCCCUUUUCAGGUUGUAUGCUUUCUCUGUGCAGGGAUAAAGUCUAUUCAUUCUGUUUUGUCUUUUACAAGAUCUAUUGCAAUGCAUUGCAGGCUCGGCAGAGUAAGUCCUAAAUAAAUGUUGACUACUCAGACCACUAACUGUUUAUUUGUGUUGUUUACCCUUAUUUUUUAUGUCCUACUCUUCAAAAGAUUACUAGAGGUGGGGUUUGCAGAAACAAAGGAGGACAUUUUUCUCAAUGAAUGUUUAAAAUUACUUCGGUGACUUGGAUAGCAAUGAAAUUUUUAAGAAUAUAUAGUCAGCUUUGGUGUGGGUGGACUUUUUGCUGUGGAAUAGAAUAAUUCCUGAAAGACUUCUAAAGUUACUUUGAAAAAAGGCAGGAAUUAGGGUGGGAGGUGGGAGAGGAGCAGAAAAAAUAACUAUUGAGUAACCAGGCUUACUAUCUGGGUGACCAAAUAAUCCAUACAACAAACCCCCGUGACAUGAGUUUACCUAUAAAACAAACAUGCACAUGUACCCCUGAACUUAAAAUAAAAGUUAAAAAAGAAGAAAGGUAGGAUUUAAUGAUUGAUAGCUUAAAGUUCUCAUCAAAUUUUUUGUAAUGAGGGAAGAAAAUAUUUCCCCAAAGCAGAACUGCAUUCCCAGAAAGAACAUUUCUUCACAUCAUGAAUAUGUGAGGAAAAAAUGUAUUUUAAACAACUGAUAGGUACAGACCCUAGGAACCUGCAUUCUAGCCCCAAUGUUGCCACUCAGUGACAUCUGCUAUGUGACUUUAGACAAAUCACUUAGUCCCUCUCAUCUUCAGUUUCCUUAUAUGUUAAGUGAUAAAGUUAAUGUAGAUUUGCUUUUUUCCUUCUGGCUCCAGAAAUCUAUAGUUUUUAUCUGUGUGUUUGUGUGUGUGUGUGCUUUCCUCUUAGAAAGCUGUAGUAUUGCUUUAAACUCUUUGAAGUUACUAAGUGAUUCAAUCUAGUGGAGUCAGUGUAUUUUAAGAGUUUUGAAAAACAGCCAUAACAAAAACAACAAAAUGUGAAGUUACAAGGUGGGGCUAUAAAUUAAUGAGUUUGUUUUUUGAAUAGCUGGCAGUUUUGUAAUUUAUUUAAUAACACUUAUACAGAACACAAUACGAUAAUCUUUAAUCUUUAUAAUUGAGAUAGGUGCAGUUAUCAUCAUUUUACAGAUGAAGAACCUGAGGCAGUCGUGUCCAUUGUGAACUCCAAUAAGAAAGAUUAAAAAGAAGGAAGAAAAAGUCCGCUGUAGAAAUGAAAAAACAAAUUUAUCCAUUGUGACAUCGUUUAGAAAUAGCAGUCAGAAUUUAACCAAGAAAGUCUGGCUCUAUGUUCUUGAUCAUUUCCCUCUAUUGCCUGUUUAAGAUAUCCAAAUAUCAUAUCUUUGAAGGUAGUCAACUUGGAGUUUAAUUCCGUUGAUCUCUCUUUUCAAAACAUAUUUUGAGUUGUUUCGGGAUCAUUUUCCAGAGACUAAGACAAAGCCCUGUGGAAAACCAAGCCACAUGUUACUCAAAGUAAUAGUGUAGGAGGAACAAGAGCCAGCAGGGAAACACAGAGGAAAUUAUUAGAAAUAUAGGAGAAUUGGAAGAGUACAGAUGAAGGAAAAUAAAUCAACUUGUUUAUGUUAUUUUAAAACCUAGAGGUCAAGGAAGAGUUCAGAAAACGAGGCUGUCAGUGGUAUCAGAUGUUAUAGCGCUCCCUAAGAAUGAGAAAUGAAAGAAACUCAUUUGUCUUGUGUAAACAUUAAAAUCAUUGGUAACUUGAGAUUACAUUUAUUGUAGAGUAAUCAGAACAGAAUCCAGAAAAGAGAUAGAAGAGAAUGGGAAAGAAAAACAAUGGUUUGGUAAAUCUGACACUGGAAGGAAAUGGAGAUAGCCUAGAUAUAGAUAAGGAGAAGAGAACUAAGAGUGUGUAUGUAUGUGUUUGUGUUAAGGACAGGAGAGAUAUAGGGAUAGGGUAUAAGGUAAAUAAGGACUAUUGUAGUUAGUUUAUAUACAUAUAAGAAUAGAGUUUAUGUUUUAUGCUUGACAGAUGUUCUAAAGGAAAAUAAACAAGUCAUUGUUCCUCCUCUGUAUUGUUUUCUGUUUAAAGUAAAAGCAUGGAGAAAGUUGAACAGUUUUUGUUUAUUUGCAGUAGGACUACAGAAAAGAAAAAUAAAAGAGCGUAUGGAAUUAAAACCAGAUUUUUGAAAAAUCAAAUCAUAUUUAAAGUACUGCUUGAGAUAUCAAAAGUCUUUUAAAUCUUAAAUACAGAGCUGGUUUUUAAUAAUGGUAAAGAGUUUUCAAAAUGUUAAAGUUUAUAGAACUAUUUCUCAUUUAAUUAUAUGUAAAUGGUUUUAUAAUUUUUUCUCACAUUAAGUUAGAAAACUAGCAAAGUAACCUACAUAAAAUUUGGUAUAACCUUUCUUAUGAUGUCACAAAACUUAAUUAUGGAGGAAGCAAUUAUUAUAAUUAGGAAAAAUUGAUGACUUAUGAUCUGACUCAGGAUCAAGGUCUGAAACACUCAUGUCAUUUCCUCCCCUCUCCUAUAUAGUAUACAGUGAUUUGUUCAUUUUGGACUCUUAAUAUUUUAACUUUUGACACCAUCAGCAAAUCUAAACACUGACAGUUGGUGUUUUCCUGAAAAAUGUUAAGGCUAAUAAUUGUGUGAUAUUUAUUUCAACACAUUGCUGCUAGUCUUCUAUAAAGAUCUCAUUAUGGGUAGGCUUUGAAGAGAUAUCCAGUUCAUAAUAUGGGCAUCACACUGGAAGCCUGCAAGAUGGAUGAUUGGCUGAGAGUAGGAGUGUAGUUUCUAAAUAAUAAUAAGUCUGUUUCCCCUGCUAGGAAGUACCCUGAGGGCAGGAACCCUCUAUCUUAGUCAUGACUUUGUUCCCAAUACAUGGUAUAUCAGGCAUGUAGCAGGUAUUCAAUAAACAUUGAAUGAAUAAAUGAACAAAUUAAUUAGAUACCAAAUCCAUCAGUUUGACACUAUAUUCUAAAUUAGUUUAUAUAGUCACCGUAAUGUGAUAAAGAAAUUGUGAUAGUCUAGUUUACUGAGCAUUGUUAUCAGGACCAUCUGUGUCUCAUGUUUAAGUCUAGAAAUCAGUCUUUGAAAAUGAGUGAAUUCAAAUGCAUUUUUAAAAGUCUAAGUGCCAUUUUGCAUGAGGGAAAUUAUAUACCUAGUAAGAAUUUCUCUGGGUUUCAAAGUCAGAACACUGAUCUUGGUAAUACAUGGACAGAAAGGAUUAUUUUUCAGUUAGGGUGUUAAACAGAUUGUGCUAUCAUUUUAACCUCUGGAAUGAAUAAGCCCCAGAUUUAAUAAGCUCCUUAUGUAUAAGAUGCCUGUUAUAAUGUGUCUGUAAUGUCCUAGAAAGAUGAGACUACCCCUGCAUAGUGCUUAUUUCUUGCAUGGAAUGAAUUUAAGAUAAGCUUGUCAAAUUUUAAAUCUGACAUAGACUAUCUUUUGAAUAAUUUAUUUGGAGUCAUCUCUGUCUGAUUAUAAUAUGCCCUAAAAUAAAUCUUGAAAAAUUAAAAUAUAUCAUACAGAAUAAACAGUCUACAUGUAACAGUUAACAGUUACAUGUAAAGUGUUAUUCAGAUUACAUUUUACAACUAUUUCUUUUCUGAUUCCAUUUUUUAUUGAAUAGAAGUUCAAUAAAUUUUAUUCUGUUAAGAAUGAGUCUGUCUUGGAGAGGGUCAGUGUCACAUAUUUACUUUGAAGUUCCUUAAAGAGGUUAGUUGAAUUCUCCCCCCAAAAUGUGCUUUGAAUUAGCAGCUUUUGAAUAUCUAUUCUAGUAGAGGUAGGAGCAAUAUGAACUAGAGAGAAUGAUAUGCAAUAAAAAUAAUAAUUUUUCUUUGACUUUGGAAUGAGGAUAAUCUAAACCACAGCCAUGUAGGCAGACAUUUUCUGAUGUAUGUAGGUAUGUUUGCAUGUCUGUCUAUCUAUCCAUCUCCUUGUUUUCUAUAUAUUUGACCCUAACCUUUCAGGCUCCUAUUUUGCCAUCAGGUCCAAAACCAAACUGAGCGAUAAGAGAGUGGAGAUCCUUAAAUCAGUGGUUCUCAAACUUUUUGGUUUCCACAUUCCUUUAUGUUUUCAAAGAAACAUUAAUGAGAAGAGUAGCAUUUUGUUAACAUUAAGAAAAACCUCUUUAAUAACUGGCUUAAUAGAAACCAGCUGGAUUCUUAUAUCUGUUCUUUUUGGUCAAAAUAUAUGAAGAAAAUCCAGCCUCACACAGAGAUGUAAUUGGAAAGGAAGGACUAUUUUAAAAGCCUUUCAGAUAAUUGUGGGUAUUCUUUGAUGCUACACCAAAAUGCAACAAGAGGUAGUUUCUUAAAGGUUAGUUGCAACACGGAAGCCAAAUCUGUGAACUUUUAGUACUCUGAAAUUAAAAUCCAUUGGUUGAUCUUGCACUUUGAAUGGAUCUUUUACCUGUGCAAGGUUUUGUUACAUCAUACAUUGGUCAUUUGAAAAUACUGGUUCACUGAGUUAUGCAGAUCUUCCAAAUGUUGACACAUUUUAUUAUGUAUUAAAAUGUCACAUUCUUUAAUACUAUCACAAAUCUUAUCAGAAAAGUCUUUAAAUAUUGUGAGCAGUUCAUGGUAGCAGAUAGAAGUUUUCCAAAAUUCUAGUUUUCACUUGAGGGUUCAAAUUUUAUCAUUGUCAAAAAUAUGUCAGUUUUCCUUGAAGUGGUAGAUUCACUAAUUUAUUUUCAAGAACAUAUCUGUCAGAUACCCAAGGCUAAACAACUAUAAUUUAUCAGUCUUUCAAGUAAAAGUGGUGUUCCAUGAAGAAAGUAGCUAGUGCAGCUCACAACUCAGUUACACAAGUGGUUUUCCUCUAGACAACAAUUGUACUUUGAUAUGCAGCAGAAAUGCUUUAUGUGUAUUUCCCAUUUUGUCGUACAGAAUAUUAAAAAGACUUCUACUCAAGGGUCAAGAUUUCAUAAAAUUAAUAACUUUUAUUGCUUCAUCAAAGACUUCCUUCAAUUACAUUGACUGUGUGUGGUAUGUGCAUGUAUAUGAACAUAGGGCAGUAAUAUGAUGAACUAUAUAAUACAGUUUGAUGUUGCUGUCUUAAUUCAUGCUAGGGCACCAUCAUUGCUUUUGCAUCAUCAGUGUAAAUAUCAACACAGUUGUUUCAAGAUAAAUGAUGAGAUUUAAGAAAGUUAUUCAACACUGAAUAUUUCAGUACUGUUAGUGUUUGUUGCCAAGCAUUCCUAUAAAAGGUCUUUGUUGUUGAUUACUUGGGGCUCAUACUGAAUAAAUCUAAGCAAAACAUAAAGUUUAUAGAUUCUUCCAUUUGUAAAACAAAAGCACAAUUCUGUAGUUGAGAUAUUAACUCAGCCUUCGUAUUUGCAACUAAGUGUAAUUUGAUGAAUUAACAUAUGGUUGGAAAGUGUCAUGAUUUCUUAUACUGACUUUUCAGCAGGCAUUGAGCAAGGUCGAUUAUCCACAAUUUUAUUAGUCUCUCAGCUAUUAUAUGCACUUUUUCAGUCAUUGCAUUAUAUUAAUAACUUACAAUGUAGGAUACUUCCGUGGUCUUUUCAUUUCCAGUAUGAUAAGCUGUAAUAGAAUUUUUUUUUAGAGGAUUCUUCACACCUGUGUUUAAAAUAUCCAGUUCCAUUUUCUUUGAACUCUACAUGAUUGGUUUCAGAAUGACAUCACAACUUAAUUGGCACCAUUAUAGUAUUUGAAAGAUUUUGUUGCAUAAGCGACAAGAAGAUAGAUUAUUCAUAUGUCUGAAACAAGAGAAAGAUGGCUUUCAAUGUAUGGUCAUUUUUUAUUAACAAUUUUGACCAGUUUCUUUGCUAGAUUCCACCUUUCCGUGAGUCAUAAAAUUCUCAAAUAUAUCAGUUUUAUCUUUUCUGUAUCUUAUAUGUAGACAGUAUAGUUGUGGGUUAAGGAGGCAAGUUUUCUAAUCUCCUGUCUUUUAAGCCAGCAAUUCAUUCUUAAAUAUAAGAAAAGUAUGUAAUAGAUUUUUAUAUGAAAUAUUAAAAUUUAAGAAGCUGUAGAUAGAUUUAGAAAACUUUUCCAAAAAGAUUUAAAAAUAAUAUUAUAAAACAAAACAAAGUAUACAUUCUUCUUUGUUGUAUUUAGAUAGAAGUUUCAGUAGUGGAGUCCAUAUAACUAAGCUCCAUAAUAAUGUGUUUCAUAACUUUCUCCAUUAUUCUACUACUAGAUCAUAGAAGGCUUGUUUCUCUUAAGGUUUAGUUUUUUCAUGCACUCAGAAAAUAGUUUUUCAGGAAGUAUGUACUGAGUAUUCUGAGGAUAUGCAAGGAGCAUGGGUUCCAGUGAUAAAUAAUACAUAGUCUCUGUGCUCAGGGAACUUAUAGUUUAGUUGGUGCUAACCAGAUAAAUUAGCAAAAUAAUUGACAGAUAUAGUAAGCAUGAUGAAAACACACAAUGGACUCAGAGAAUAACAAGGAUGCUCUCCUGAGACAGCGACAUUUAGCUGAUAUCUCAAACAUGGGGGGAAUUCAAGGAUUCCAGGCAGAGGAAAGAGCAUAUGAAGGCAGUUAAGUAAGGCAGGAAAGAGCUUUAUUUGAGGCACUGAAAGAAAACCAAUGUGACAGGAGACUAGUGAAUGGGAAGGGGGAUGAGUAAUGAAAAUGAGGUUUGGGAGAUUGGAAGGGGCUAGUUCUACAAAGCCUUAUGAGCUAUAGUAAGUAGUUUGGGUUUUAUUCUGAGGGCCAGCAAAGGGAUUUAAGCAGCAGAAUAACACGAAUGAUUUAGUUCGUAGAAGAUGUUCACUGCUACAUGGACAAUGCAUUAGAGAGAGACCUAUUAACAGUAGGAGCAGAGAGAGCAGAGAUACCAAUUAGAAGGCUUUUUCAGUAGCUCCGGCAAAAUGAUGAUGGCAGCAAAGUGAUGAAUGGAUUCUAAAUACAUUUUGUGGAUAGAUUUAGUGAGAAUUGGAGAGAUAUUAGAUGUGUUCAGAUUUCUGUCUUGAAUUACUAGGUAGAAAGGACUAUCAUUUUUUACUAAGAUGAAAAUAUUUGGGGGGCACGGUAAUAUGUUUGGUAUAAAUGUGGAGAGUUAUUUUUGGAUACAUUUAAAUUUGAAAUGUCUGUGAGACAUUCAAGGGAAUGUGUGCAAUUGGCUCUGUGAAUCUGGGACUCAAGAGAGGAUAGAUCUGAGCUAAGAAGAGUAAUUAAGAAUUGUCAGCUCAUACACAUUUAUUUAUUUAUUUGGAGACGAGUCUUAUUCCAUCUCCCAGGCUGGAGUGCAAUGGUGUGAUCUCAGCCCCCUGCAACCUCUGCCUCCUGGGUUCAGAUGAUCCUCCUGCCUCAGCCUCCUGAGAAGCUGGGAUUACAAGUGUUUGCCACCACACCUGACUAAUUUUUGUAUGUUUUAGUAGAGAUAGGGUUUCACCAUGUUGGCCAAGCUGGUCUUGAACUCCCAACCUCAAGUGAUCCACCCACCUCAGCCUCCCAAAGUGUUGUGAUUAUAGGCAUGAGCCAUCACACCCGGUCAGCUUACACACAUUAUCUCAUGGAUUUACAUGGGAAUAAUGGAGUCAUCAAGAAGAGAGUAUAUAGAGAGAGGAGGGUUCAGGACCAAAUUAGAUUUUGAAUUGGAGAAGGAUGAGAGCAGCAAAGGACGGUUCAGGACCAAAUUAGAUUUUGAAUUGGAGAAGGAUGAGAGCAGCAAAGGAGGAGGGUUCAGGACCAAAUUAGAUUUUGAAUUGGAGAAGGAUGAGAGCAGCAAAGGAGACUAAAUAGGAGCGGUCAGCAAAUAGGGAGAAAACCAAGAGAAGAGACUUUUGAAUGGGGAAGGAGUGGUUUAUUCUUGAAUACUGUUGAGACGUUAGAUAAGAUGAAGGAUUGGUUUUCACUGGAUAUGUCAACAUGAAAGUCACUGAUACACUUGACAAGAGCCUUUUAGUGAUGACAUGAAACAUAAAAGUUAAAGAUGGAUUAAGUAGUAAGGAAGUGAGAACAGCAUAACUAUUUAAAAAUGUUUGCCUAUAAAAGAAAAUAGAGAAAAGGUAGGGUUUUGUCUUAUUUUCAAACUCUAGAUAUCAAUUAUAUAUUUUAAAGGAAUGAACCCAUAGAUAGGAAGAAAGCAAUGUUAAAAGAGAAGUCGAGUCCUUGAGAAGGGGCAAAAGGGUGGAAUUCAGAUAACAGGUGGAAGGAUGGCCCUUUGCUAGUAAGGCAGGACAUUAUGGUAGAGGCAAGAUGAGUUCAUAGAUAGGACCUUAGGUUCCAGGAAGAUAAAGAGAAGACACUUCUAACAGUUUCUGUUUUCCCAGUGAAGGACAUCUCAACUGAUGUCAUCAGCUGAAAGUAAGGAUAUUAGAGGAGGUGUAGAAGAUUUAAGCAGAGAGGCACAAGUAUGAAGUAGUUGUCUUGGCCAGUGGGAUAGUGAGCCUACUAGAGACAUUUGGAUUGUGAGGCCUUGGUGGGGUGUCAGUAUGCCGUAUGCUUUAAAGUCAAAUCUCUGCAACAGAAUGCCAGGUGUAGAGUUACAGUUGAUUAAUAAGACACAGCCCCUGUACUCAAGGAGUUUGUAAUCUAGAGAAUGAAAGACAUAUAAUUACAAUAUGGUGUGAUGGUUGUGAUGAACAAGGUAAAUAUAGGGUGUCAUAAGAGCACACAUUAACCAAUCUUGGAGGGGCUGUCCUAUGCAAGGAGGUCUUCAUGGAGACCUAACAGCUAAGCUAAGACCUGCCUGUUCUGCAAGUACCUUACUUAAAGCUAUUACAUAAUAGCUGCUGGGGAUGAAAAUAUUCUAGAAGGUAUGAUAGUCACACUGUAUUAUUAUAUCUUUAUGCAGUAGCUUUUAUUUCUGCUGACAUCAUCAGGCAUCUUUGAAAUUUCUUUUUUUUUUAACACUUCGAAAUGCUGUGAAGCAAAGUAUCAUCCCUCUCUUUCCUCACCCUCUUCUCUUCCUUAACACCUUUCUUCAGUUCUAGCUGUUGGCAGCUAGAUGCAACUUAAUAAUGCCAUUUUGUUUUCAUUUGGCAUGUCAUUCAUCAUUUUCAAAAUAAAUAAACUUUAAUUUUGUGCUGCCACAAUCAGGAAUAUUUGAACAUUUAGUGCUUAUCUUGGGUAUCUGCCCUUAUUACUUUCUGAGGAGCUGCCCUUUAUAGCAAUCAGGGAACUAUACCACUUGGAAGACUAAUUGUCUUUAUACAAAAAUAAAAUCCUUGUGUUCAGAUUUCUGUCUUGAGUGGCUGGUUUGAAUCUAAUUUUCUGUUAUAUGAAGCAAAGAUUUAUUAUUUAACAUAGUUUCAAAAUUAAAAUUGAUAGUGAAAUUUUAUGUGCCAUGCAAUGUCAUGUGUGUUCUUUUAAGGUGAAGAUUCAUUUUUUAAUAGCUUUAUUGAGGUAUAAUUGACAUAUAAUAAACUGCACAUAUUUAACACCACAUUUUAUGUGUGAUAUGUAUGUGUGUGUGUGUGUGUGUGUGUAUAUAUGUAUAUACUUAUAUAGGUGAAAUCAUCACCAUAGUCAAAAUAAUCAGCAUCCCCAUCAGUCCCAAAAGUUUUGUUUCUCAUGCCCCUUUGUAAUUUUUCCCUGCCCUCUCACCAGUCAACUGAUCUUUCUGUUACUACAAAUUAGUUUAUAGUUUUAAAAAUUGUAUAUAAAGGGAUCUUAAUUAUAUAUAUUUUCCUUCCAGCAGAAUUAUUUUGAGAUUAAUCCAUGGUGUUGCUUGUAUCAGUAGUUCGUCUUUACUGCUAAUAUUCUGGUGUAGGGAUAUAGCACAAUUUACUAAUAUAUUCACCUUCUACUGUUAGCUACUACAAACAAAGCAACUGUGACUAUUUGUGUACAAGUCUUUGUAGGGACAAAUGCACUCACUUCCCUUGUGUAAAUACCUAGGAGUGGGAUGGCUGGGUUAUAUAGUAGGCAUAUGUUUAGCUUUUUAAGAAACUACCAAACUACUUUGGUACAAGUGGUUGUACCAUUUUACAUUCCCACCAGUGGGAAUAAGAGUUGCAGUGCCUCCAUAUCCUUGGCAACACUUGAUACAGCCUAUCUUUUUAUUUUUAGCCAUUCUAAUAGAGGUAUGUAGUGGUAUCUCAUUGUGGUUUUAAUUUGCAUUUCCCUAAUAACUAUAUUAAUUUUGACCAACUUUUUAUGUGCUUAUUUGCCAUCCAUAAAUCUUCUUUGGUGAAGGGUCUGUUCAAAUCUUUCCCGAUUUUUUAUUGAGUUAUUUUCUAAUGAUUGAGAUUUCAUUUUGAGGAUUUUGUGUGUGUGUUGUUUUGUUUAGCAGCUUAGAACACACACAUUUAUUAUCUCACAGUUACUAUGGGUCAGGAGUCCAGGCAUAGAUUUGCUGGGUCUUCUACUCCAGGGUUUCAUCUGAAAGUAACAAUCACAGUCUUGGCCAGGGCUGCAGUUGCAUCUCAAGGUUUUACUGGGGAAGGUUCCACUCAUAAGUUCACAUGAUUGUUGGUAGAAUUCAGCUCCUCGUGGGAUGCCGAACUAAGGGUCUCAGUUAUUUGCUCAGUUGGAGAUUCCCCUCAGUUCCUGCCACAUGGGCCUCUUGAUAUGGCAGCUCACAACAUGACAACUUGCUUCAUGAAAGCCAGCAUGGAAGUGUUUAUGUUUACUGGUUUAUUAUGAUUAACAAAGGAUACAGAUGAAUAGCCCGAUGGAAGAGAUGCAUAGGGCAAGCUAUGUGGAAGGGGUAUGGAGCUUCCAUACCCUCUCCAAGUAGGCUACCUUCCAGGCACCUCCUCAUGUUCAGCAAUCUGGAAGCUUUGCGAGUUCUUUAUGUAUUCUAUAUACAAGUCCUUUAUCAAAUACAUGACUUGUAAAUAUUUUCUCCCAGUUUUUUGCUUGUAUUUAAAUUUCCUUUUUAGUGUUUUUCAAAGGGCAGAAAUUCUUAAUUUUGAUGAAGUCCAAUAUGUCAGCUUUUUAUUUUAUGGACUGUGUUUUUAUGGUUUUAAGAAAUAUUUGCCUAACUAAAGGUCACAAAUAUUUUCUCAUAUUUUUUUUCUUAAAGUCUUACAAUUUUAGGUUUUACAUUUAGGUGUAUGAUCCAUUUUGAAUUAAUUUCUGUAUAUGUGCAAGGUGUAUAUCAAAGUUCAUUUUGUGUGUGUGGAUAUCCAGUAUUGUAUGAUAUUCAAUGCUGUGUUUUCACCUAAUAGCUUUUAAAGGAAGAAUUAAAGCAAAGCCAAGUUAAAUAGGUUAUACCAGACUGUUAGUUUUCUUUGUGUUAUCCUUGACUUUGUUAGGUUGCACAUUUUGCUGGAACUUCUUAAAACAGUAUCCUAUGAUUGAACUUCUUCAACCUCAAAUUUCCAGUCUUUAUACUUAACCAAUGAAAUGUUAUUUAUAUACUCUUUGGAAACAUAACAUAUACUGUAGAUAAUUAUAACAAAAGUGUAAUGGGUAGCAGAAGAUAUUGCCAAACCAAAAUUCUGGAGACCAGAUGAGACAAACACAUAAUAUGUGCCUGUAUGGGUCACAGUGCUAGGAAAUACACUGAAAAGUGAACAAAGAACUAAAAAUAAGCCUCUUAUAAGAAAAGCUGCUACUUCUGGGCUAAUCUAUUAGUAGUUUGUUUUCCUUAAUUUGAAAAAGAGCUUCAGAAUCAGACUCUAGAGUGAAUCUUUUAAAACUAUAUAUAUUAUGCAUGUAUACACAUAUACAUACUCUAUGCAUUGGCUUAGAUAAUAUAAAAACAGCACAGGAAUAGUUUAUGCUGUAGUAUUGUGCAGUCUUAUUCAGAAAUAAGAAAAAUAGUUUUUCCAUUUAGCUGUGAGUCAUUACUUUUUAGUUUCGUGGAGAAAUUAAGUUUUAGUGGGGGUCGAUACAGCUUUUUUUUUUUUGUAGAAAAUCAGGUAGCAUGGGCUUUGGAGUCAGACAAAUCUCGGUUUUAAUUUUCAGUGUCCUUAUCUCUAAUAUAGUAAUAUUAAUAGUUACCUCUUCCUGGGUUGUUGAGAGGUUUAAAUGAAAUAAUAAGUUAAGUACUGGCACAGUGCUUAACACAUAAUAGGUAUUCAAGAUAUGUAUACUUCUUUAUCAUCAGGGGAUUGACCUUGGAAGCAUAUGGGUACAUAGAAAGAACCCAUAAAAGGAUAUGACAAGGGGAGAGGAGUUUGUUUUCAUUAGAUUUAGCAAAUUCAUUCUUUCCCCCAACUCCCCAGAAAAAUUCAUUUUAAUGCUAUUAUUUUCCUUAUCACCCAUAAACAGACAGAAAAUUGGCAUGUUUCGAAAGAGUGUUAAAACUGCAAGAGUAUUACAUGGUAUCAUUACACUACCAUCCAUUAUCUAACUGGGUUUAUUUAUGAAGGUUAGAUUUAGAUAAUUUAGACUUACCCUUUUUCCAUUUUGUGGGGAAAGAGAAUCAGAAACUUGAAAGGAAGAGCUCUUCCAAACAGAAAGAUAGCUAGAAUCUCUCUCAAUAGUCUAUAUAAUCUCUUCUAAUAAUCUUUAGCAAAAGUGACUUUUGAGUUCUUUUAAAUAUUUCCUGUAUUGAUUCUAAUUCAGUGCUCAUUUCAUGUGAUGUCUAUAGAACUACAGACUUAGAUUACAGUCAGAAAACUGAGUAACAGCAGACACCAGGUUUUCAGCUGUUUUUAGGGUUUAUUCAGAUUGACUACAUCACAUUCAUUUGGAUGGAUUUAGUGACAUCAAUUGAUAAUUGUAAAGAAACUAGCCUUUAAUCUGACAUUUUCAUAUUGAUAUUAGAUAGGAGCCACAUGACUAUGUCAUGGGUUCAUUCACAAGAUAUAAUAAACAUUAUUUUCACUUGUAGCAUAAAAGCAGUCUUUAGUGUUAUCUUAGAAGCAUUAAAACACACACAUAUAUAAAAUCAUAUAGAUUAAAAAAUUCUAUCAGCAUAGGUUCUGUAAUUGUUAAUAGAUGUAAUUGCAUAAGGUCGCUAUGCAUUAUUUCUCAUUUUCAGAUGAAGCCUGUCACCUUGACAUUUUUAUAUAUAAUAGGAAUCCACAGGUUGUUAAAAACAUAAGGAAAUUAAGAUAAUUUGAAUUCAGAUUAUAAAAUAGUUCAGGUCUAUUCUGAUGAAGCAAUGUCACUUAGGUCUGAGGCUUUUGGGUCAGCUUUUAAAAGUUUAUCUUAUUUUUCAUUAAAAUAUGUAUGUAUAAUACUCUAUCAUGCAAAGAGAAAUGGUCAACAGAAUUUCUGUGCAUAUAUGGUUGCUGGUUAUUUGAAAGCCAUUCUCCUCCUAGGAUUAUUUGACCAAUUUUGUAUUCAGCUUAGAUUAGGGAGAAUAUAGUGUCUCCUUAGGUAAAAUACUUACUAGAACCAAAAAGUCCAGAUUAAAUUGUUUUUAUUUUUAUUUUACUGCAGUUUUGUGCAGUUGACCUGAUUUUAAAAUAUAAAACUAGGAAGGCAUAUUUUUCAUCUACCAAAAUGUGAAUCUUACUUUCAUUUUGAAACAAACACCUCUGCUUUAAGAAGAUGAACGGUAGUGAUAAAUACAAAAACGUUAAAAUUUUUUAAAUGAAUAGCGUUUGUUGAUCUUUAAAGAAAACAUAAAUGUGAAAUAACUUUAGAGCUUAAAAGUUUUCUUCCUCAAACCUUUUAGGAAUUGAUUUUAUUAUCCAAAACAACUUUAUUCAUACUAAGUGUGACUAUCUGAAUAAUUACCUUACUUUUAUAGUUUUUUUUUUAAAAAAGCUCUUCUAACUGUAAUUAUCCUCAAAGAAUUGGAUUAAGAAAUUCAAUAAUUUUCUGUCAUUAGUCCAGCGAGAUAUUUACUGAAUAGCCAUUACGUUCCUGGCUGUUAACACUACAAGGACUCCAGCAAUGAGCAAAGCAAACAAGCCCUUGCUUUUCCAGAGCCCACAUUCUAGAGUCAGAUGCUAAACAAAUACACAGAUACAUAUAUAAUAAAAUAUUGGUUUAAGUGUUGAAAAGCAAAAUCAGAGUAAGAAGGCAGGUAGUCAUUUUAAAUUAACAUUGAGAAAUGUUUCCAUUUUAAGCAUAUAAAUUCUUUGGCUUCUCUUUUUAAAUUUGCUUUUGACUGUUUGUUGCUGGCGAAAAUUAUUUAAAGUAAUUAGGAACUCAUCGUAAAUAUUUUGUACACUACUCUAAAAAUCUAAUUCCAACUAGUGAAUUUAGCAUUUAUAAAUGGAGGUGUCUAUAGAGGAAUAAAAUCUUUGGUUAACCACUACUUUACUUUUAGCAGUAAAGUCUGCAGCUCAUGAAAUUUGUAAUUCUGGAGUGGUUUCAGUUUGCACCAUCCCCUGGGGAGCCUGUUGAUACAGCACUGAGCUACAGAUUAUUAUUCAGCUGUAGAAGUUUUAUGCUUAGGCAUUUUCUUACAUCUUCUUCUCUCAGUCAGUUGAAAUCUUGUAUUUUUGCCAAAUAAAACAAAUCCUAUAUUAAUAAGAAGCUAUAAAUAAACAGUAGGAGCAUGAGUCAGAGCCAGCAUCACCCCAUUCCUUGUGUGUACCUCUCUAGUACUCCCCAGUAUGUUCCUUUUGCACAAACAUGUAGUACUGCGUAACUACUGUUCUACAGAUGAACUCCAGUUAUUUAAGUGAGGCCUGUUUUUUAGAACUAAGUAAUACUGUAACUAGUAGAAUUCUGGCAUGUUACCACAGUCAAAAGCAGAAUGUGAAGCUGUAUGCUAUUGAUGGGAGGAAAAAAGAAAUAUAUUUCCUACCUUUCCUGUAUAAAGCCCAGAAGAUUCCUGUUAGAUUUCCAAAAUGGGUUUUUAUAUAAUAUAAUAUAAUUCAACAUUUUUUUCAGAGGAAAAAAGAAAAAGAUAAGUUGCUUGAAAGUCCCAUCUCUUUUGCUAGUCGGCUUCUGUCUGAUAAAAUUUUAUUCUGUUUUGCUUCAUUGUUUAUUCAUUCAGUAGAUGUUCAUUGAACACUUACUGUUACCAGGCACUGUGCUACCAUAGACGGUAUAAAGACAAAUAAGCUAAAAUCCUUGUUCUCAAGGAAUUUAUUAUUGUAGAGAAAAGUGACUUGUAAAUCCAAAAUUUCAUACUGGGAUAGGAACUAUAAAAGAGACAUCCUGCAGAAUACUGAGAUUAUAAAUAAAACUAGUAUGUUUGAAGCAUUUAGUGUCCUAGCUGUUUUAUAGAAGUCAUUUCAUUUAAUCCUUUCAACAGCUUUAUGAGGUAGAUAUCAUUACACUAUUUUACUUGUGCCAAGAGCACUACAUUCAUCAAGGAAGGAGGAGGUAGUAUCAAAUUUUUCAGAAAACAAGAGAGUUGGUUAUAGAAGGAUGAGUAGGGUAGAGAGUAGGAGGAAGAUGAGGCAGUGUGGCAUUUCAGACAGAGAGGUGAAUAUGUAAGCACACAGGAUGAGUGAGAGAAUUGUUGGAAUGUAGUCAGUUCUAGGAAAUAAAAGAUGGCAGGGUCCAGAUCAUGAAGUUUGGUUCUUAACCUGUAGAAGACAGAAAUAUGAUCAGACUUGCAUUUCAGGAAGAUAACUCUGUAAUUGUUUGCAAUUCCUGUUAAACGAAGAAAUUUUCUCCAGCAUUGACUUAUGUUUAUUAAAUACAUAUAAAAACUAAAUUCUAGAAACAUCUUAUACAGUUAUACAUCACUUAGCAAUGGGAUACAUUCUAGGAAAUGCAUUGUCAGGCAAUUUCUUCAUUGUACAAACGUCAUAGAGUAUACUUACACAAACCUAGAUGUAUAUCUUUGUUUAUAUUUAUUUUUUCAUAUGGAAAACCAAAUUUCUUAGCCAUGUUACUGAAUGUCAGUCAUUUCCCUUACUUGAUCUGCAUCACCAACAUUAAGUGCCAUGUAUCAGAUUUCUGUAUAUGUUCCAUUAUAAUCUCAUGGGACCACCAUAGUACAUGCGGUCCAUUGUUGACAGACACAUCAUUAUGUGGUGCGUAAGUGUACUUAUAGUUUUACAACUACAAAGUGAAGCACAGAGAGGUUACAUAACUUAGCCAGUGUCACACAGCUAAUAAGUAGCAAAGUCAGGAUUCGACAUGUUAAGCCAACUUCAUGGACUUAACCACAGUCCUGUAUUGCCACUCCUCUUCAUUUAAAGGCAUGCAUGCACAUAUUAGAUUUGGAGACAGUUCUAGAGACACUGAAUUGGCAACUACAGUCGACAAAGAGACAUUGCAGCAAGUACCUCUACGUUGUUUGUUUCUGUACCCUUAACUUGCAGUGGUCUACAAGAAAGAAUGAAGGAAGGGAAGUGAUAUAUUUGUCAACCCUAACUACAUUGUAAAAUGAAGCUUUUUUUUUUUCUUUUUUUGAGAGGGAGUCUCGCUUUGUCACCCAUACUGGAGUGCAGUGGUGCGAUCUCAGCUCACUGCAACCUCCACCUCCCGGGUUCAAUCUGUUCUCCUGCCUAAGCCUCCCGAGUGGCUGGAAUUACAGGCAUAUGCCACCACACCUGGCUAAUUUUUGUGCUUUUUUUUUUUUAGUAGAGACGGGGUUUCACCAUGUUGGCCAGUCUGGUCUCGAGCUCCUGACCUCAACUGAUCCGCCUGCCUUGGCCUCCUAAAGUGCUGGGAUUACAGGCUUGAGCCACUGCACUCGGCCUGAAGCAUUUUAUGAUGCUCACUACCAAGUGUUCAUAAGCGGUAAAUAAAGCCCUUGGGCUAGGUAAUGUAAGAUCCAUUGCAACCUGGAGAUGAAGAACUUUGUAAAGGGGAUAAUUGUUAUCACCCAUCAGAGCAUCAGAGUUUUAAGAUGAUCUAGAUUUAGUCCCACUAAUUAUAUUUCUCCUAACUUUUAUAGACAGAGAAAUCAGUGAAAAAUAUGUAUUUCUAAGGAUUAAAUCCCAAUCCAUAGCUCAAGGCUACCUUUAUGUCUAAUAGUUGUGAUAUAAUAUGUUGCUUAGAAUAGGUUCUAUAAAUGGAAUUCACACAUAGGACCCCAGAAUCGCUUCUUCACAGGGUUUCAGAGUUGGAGGACAUAUAAAAGGAUAAAUCAAUCCAUAAAUCUCUAAGUAUUCCUAAAAGAAGAGUGGUGUGUCAGUUAUUGGCACCAGUACAUCAUGAAUCCUGCUGGGCUGUGGAGAAAGGAGAAACUAACCUGAACAAGACUAUACUCUACACAGCUGUCCCUGACAUUCUACCACCUGUUAGCAUUCAGUAUUAAUUUCAUGGAUCAAAUCAAGGCAUGCAAGUGCAUUAAAUAACUUUUUAAAAAACAACUGCUGAUUGCUGACGUCUAUGAGGGAAGAAAAAUUAGGGGCUGUUAUUUUCCUAUCAACCAUCACUCUCAUUAACAAGAACAGGAAACAUUACGAAUAAAUAAAACUCUUACAUCAUACCAGAAAAAAGAACAGCUGAAUCCCCUAAAGGAUUUCAUAUUCUAUCAUCAGACAACGAAAGAAAAUAAUUCCAUAUAAAUGGCUGCAUGAAUCAUUGAAAGAAACUUCCCUGCUUUUUUAAAAGAGCAACUAGAAGUAUUUACUUUUUGAAAAUAGAGUAACCAUUUGUUAAACCGUAUAUACCAUUGAAGAUGUUUUGGGUAUAAAAGGGAAUUUCCAUAAUAAUUACAUAGUAAUCUUUUAUAGCCAAAGUUAUGAAGAAGAUCAGGAUUUGGGAAAAUUGUGGUCAAUAUUUGAUUUUCCUUUUCUGUUUGAUAGCCUUAUCUAAAUUCCCCUAGCUUGAAUGUAGUAAAUAUGAGUGUGUAAAAAUGUGUAUCUAAUUCACCUCUUGGGGGAGGUUUAAUGUAACUAUAAAUAAAAAUUCUUUCCCCAGGUUAAAAAAAAAGUUACAUAGUGUUUAAUUCUACCUUUUCUCAUUUCUCUAUAUCCAAAACUAUCACCAAGUACUGUUAAUUUUACUUUAUAAAGCUCUCUUGAUAUGUCUCUUCAACCUCAUCACCACUGCUUUAAAUGAGGCAUACUUCCUCAUUUGGAUUAUGGCAGCAGUCUCUCUUCCUUUAGUCUCUCCUUCAAAUCCACCUCCAUCCUUCAUAUCAUCCAUCAUGUAUUUUUCCCUGCCUAAAUUCCUUGGUUGGCUUCUAUUAAAUCCAAGUUCCUUAAGCAUGGCAAACAGGGGCCAGCUUCCACGAGCUGGUCCAUACCUCUCCUGCCUUAUUUCCUGACACUUUCCCUUAUACCUUGAGAUCCAGCUUGCCAGUAUUUCCCCAAUACCUCCACCGCAUAUACAACCACAUACAUAUACACCCUUAUCCCCUCCCUCAUGUACCACCCAUAUAUAAUUCUCUUUACCGCAUCCUUUAUCACACUCCUACAAGCCUUGAAGCAAUCUGAACAUAGAAACCAUCUUUGAUUUUCAACUCCUAAUUGGGACUGAACAUACUUGUCUUGAACACAGAUUGCUGCCUUGUUAGUAUAGGUAUCCUAAUAUGGCACAUGUGUAUAGUUGAAGCUAUAAUGCAUUCCCCAAGUUCCCUUUCAGGACUAAAGGGUUAUUUCCCAACAGCUGGAAGUCCUGCUGCCAGACAGCCUUCUUCAGGAAUUGCCUUGUCCCCAACUCAAGACAACCCUGAAGGACCUUUCCCAGUUUUCCAUGGGGUCCACUGAGGCCUUGAGAUUGUACUGAAGUCAACUUCUCCCUCUGCUGUCGCUUCCCUUCCACAGGUGUUUAUCACAAGAACAAUCCUUAAUAAACUUCCUGUAAGCACACUCUCAGAGUCAGCUUGCUGGGGAACCCAAGCUAUAACAACAUGUUUAUCUUGUUCACACUUUCUUCUGAGUUCUAAAUCAUGGGAAGUUACAGUUAUCCAAAAUCUUACUAAUUGGAAGAUCAUUUCAUCAGACGUGUAUUGAGCACCUGCUUCAUGUCAGGCAUUGUGCCAGAUACAAUGGAAACAAAUCAAGACUUGGCCUCUGUCCUUGAGUUUACAGUCUGAGGUGACAGUUACAUAUGAACCUAACUGUAUUAAAGCAUCUUGAGAAUCUUUUUGAUUCAAAUGUCAAUAAUUUUAGUAUAAAAUUCAAAAGCAUGGAUUUUGUGGUGUUACAAAGAACAAAAGGAAAAUAUUUCAGGGGAAGGAAAAUGAAUAUAAAUAAGUAGAAUGAAAUUUUAGAAGAGCACAGAAUUUGUCUUUAUAAUUCUGAAAGCCUUUAGGGAAAAGGUAAUUUUUUCACUUUUUAUUUUGACAUAAUUUCAAACUUACAGAAAAGUCACAUGAAUACUGAACUCCCAUACACCCUUUAUGCAGAUAUAUCAGUUUUUAACAUUUUCCCUCAUUCUGUUUCUUUACACACAUACAAAUUAUUUUUGUGAACUCUCUGAGAACAGGUUAAAUACUACAUUAUAUCACUUCAUACCUUAAAAAUGUAGUAUUUCCUAGAAACAAGGGUAUUCACCUCCAUAACCACAAUGCAGUUGUCAAAUUCAGGUAAUUUGACCUUGAUCUUUAAUCUACAGUCCAGAUUCAGAUUUUGUUAAUUGUCCCCAAAAAGAUGAGUUUAGGAAGAGUCAUAUAACUUAACAUUUGUAAUGUAAAUUAAAGAUCUCGGAAGUUUGCUAACCUGAUUUAAAUACCACAGUGAAAUGAACCACUUCUGAUUUUCUACGGAGAAAGCAAGGGUUAGGUCCAGGUUACCUGUAAAGGUGUGACUUAGGGCUCCCCAGAAGUGAACCUUGCUCUGGAGACCCCAUUUGGUGAGGUUCUUUUCAAAAGAGAUUGUAUAUUUUUGACCCAGGGAUUGUCGAUUUGUUGAGCUCCCAUGUAAGUAUGCCGCCUUGCCAUUGACAGGUCUUCACAAUGCUUUCUUAAACGACAUUCUUUGGAACUGUCUUUCAUAGUCAGGCGACCCGCCAGCCAGGCCGCCAGGUAGGUGGAAGGGCGGCUUCGGGAACUAGAUCCGGCUGGUUCUCUGCUAACAUGUGGUCCUCGAUGCUCUAGCGGAUUGGCCCCAAACCUCAGCACACAGAGCUUUGGUAGGGCUGGGGAUGCAGGUCAGCCUGCUGAAGGCGUCUAGAGGACUUGGGCGGGGGCGUGACUUCCUGCUGCACCACUUCCUUUCCAGCCACGUGGGCUUCUGGGACCCUAUGACAUAAUUUCUGGAGUGGUCUGUUGGGAGUUGUGGCGGCGGCGAGGCCCAAGCACAGCUGGCCAAGGCGGGUGUAAAACGCGGGUCGUGUCCACCCCAAAGCUCGACGCCUCUAGAAGCCAUGGCUUUUCUGCUGAAGCUAGAGCCGGACAUGCAGGGGAAAGUAGAUUUGUUUCGAGCCCGUAUCGCCCAGGAGGCCGAGGAUCUCGUGUCCACCUUCUUUCCUCAGAAGGUCUUGGAGCUGAAUAGCCGAGUUCAGGAGCUCCGGCUGCAAGACCUGUCCAGAAUCCAUUCGGUGCCAACCUCGGAGCCCCUGGCCACCCCAGGCAACAAGGGAGAUGGGCCCAACCAAAAUCUGCCAGUUCUGCUGACUCAGUUCUCCAUCAAGGUCCCAGCACUGCUUGGCAGCGAGGGACAGCUUCUGCGGAGCAACCAGCAUCUGGUGGAGUUGACUGAGUGGGUGAAACCUGAGAUCAAGCUGCUGAGAGAGAAAUGCAACACAGUGCACAUGUAGGUGCACCCGCUUAUCCUGAAGGUGCAGGACGGCAACAACUUCAGGGUGUCUAUCCAGGAAGACACUGUGGACCAGCUGUGGACCGUGGAUAGCACAGCGGCCUCCUCUCUAUGCGGCUUCUCCACCUACUACAACACCCAGGCCAAGUUGGUAUCCAAGAUAGUGAAGUACCCCCAAGUGGAAGAUUAUCGCUGCACUGUAGCAGAGGUCGACGAAAACGAGUACCUGAGUGUGCGCCAGAUCCUGCUGCACCUACGGAACGAGUAUGCCACCUUGCGUGAUGUAAUCCUUAAAAACAUUGAGAAGAUCAAGAUCCCUCGGAGCACCAACCGUGAUAACCUAUACUGAUAGCCUUUCUCCACCCCAUUUGCCUUCAGGAGUUGGCGGAGCUGUUUAGGCACCUAGAAGGCUGGUUAUUAAUGACUCUACAGGUCAUGAAAUUACUGGAAAUGUGUGUUACCAUUUAGAAUUUCAUACAGCUUAUCCUCAUACUGAAUCAUCUUUUGGUGUAAUUUUUAUUUGAUUUUCCUUUUGUGAGGAGAAUGGGGACAAACCAUCAAAAAGAAAAGACUGCCAUUUUUAAAAGCAGCUUUAUAGAUAAAUGUUGGCCCAAGGUUUCUUUAUUAUGGCCUUAGCGACAUUGAAUGGUUUUAGGGGCUACUUAAAAACUAAAUCUUAAAGUUAAAUGAAGUUUUUCCUAAAGUUCUGCUAUCCGUUGAACUUUGUUCAAACUUACAGAAAUGCUCCUUUUACAGCAUCAUUUUUCUUUUUUUGCGAGGAACGGAGUUUAAAGGGAUAUGUUUAGGUCAUUGUAUGCCUCCAGUUUAACAGAUUGAAAUAAAACUUGGUUAUAAAAUUU